CUCGCCGCACCCGCCUGUGUGGGGCGCCCUGCGUUCCCGGGGGGGGGGGCAGCAGGAUCUGCGGGUGGCCGAUCAGGGUCCCCGGCUGCUGGGUGCCCCCUCCUGCCCUGUGGGGGUGCCUGUGCCCCCCGUGCCACCGGUUCUCCCCCAGCUCUCCCCCAAACAGGGACAGGUGAGUGGGGCCGGGUGUCGGGGCCUGGCACAGGGCUGCUGGCUGCCCCGGGAGCGAUUGCCGGGUCCGGCUGGGACGCGCGUGUGAGUGCGUAUGCGUUUGUGUGUGCGUGUGGCUGCUGUCCAGGGGUGUCUUUUGCUCUGUGUACACACACCAGGUGGGUGCCAGCUAUCCUCCGGGUCCCCAAGGGGUCAGCAGCUGCUGAGACAGCCCCUUGGACAAGCCCCUGACCCGGGAGCCCCCGGUCCCUGCUGGGAGGCGGGAUGGGUUGUGGCAUCGGCUGGCACAGCUGUGUGGCUCCCAGGGCUGGGUGAUCGAUGGCCCGGCACAGCCGCCUCUGUCGCCGGAGCGCCCACACCCAUUUGUCAUCCACAUGGGUGGGGGGGGCGGCGGGCAGGGAGAAGGGGCCGCCUCUGCACCCACCACCCAGUCCAGGCCGGGUCUGCAGCCCCUCGGGGAGCCCCAGGACCUCUCCUGGCCCAGCCCCUGCCUCCCGACCGCCACCCUGUCUCAGCCACAGACCAGCUGGUCAGCCUCUGCCUGCCCCUGCAGCCCGUGACUGCCCUGCAGGGCCCCAAGCCUUUGGACGAGUGGACUUCUCCAGCCCUGUUGGUCGUCCCCCCAACGGCACCAACACAGUGUUUUGGGGGCAGCAGACAGCAGUGCCCCAGCCCUACCCUGCUCAACCCACUGGCCAUGCAUGACCACGGGUGCGACCCCCAGCCAGGCUUUGAACAGGCAGAUUGGCAGGGGCCAGGGUUGCUGGAGGGAAUGAGACCAGGAGGCUGACGUCCACCCGAAGUGGCCAUGGUGCCCGGCCCUGCCUCAUAGCAGGCUGCCAUGUCGCGGGAGGCGGGCUCAUGCCGCGUGGGCACAGGGGCGAGGGCGCGGUCUCGGAAGCCCAAGAAGCCACACUACAUCCCGCGGCCCUGGGGCAAACCCUACAACUACAAAUGCUUCCAGUGCCCCUUCACCUGCCUGGAGAAGUCACACCUCUACAACCACAUGAAGUACAGCCUCUGCAAGGACUCCCUGUCCCUGCUGCUAGACUCCCCAGACUGGGCGUGCCGCCGUGGCUCCACCACGCCUAGGCCCCACGCACCCACCCCAGACCGCCCUGGGGAGUCCGACCCCGGCAGGCAACCCCAGGGAGCACGGCCCACAGGUGCUGCCCCCGCGCCUGACCUCGUGGUCGCCGACAUCCACUCCCUGCACUGUGGCGGAGGCCCCAAGUCCAGGGCCAAGGGGUCCCCAGGGCCACCACCCCCUGUGGCUAGGGCCACCCGGAAGGGUCCCGGCCCCAGUGGGCUCCUGCCUGAGUCGUGGAAGCCGGGGAUGGGAGGGGACCCAAGGGGCGUGGGUGCGGGGGACAUGGCCUCAGCAGGCCCUGAGGGCAGCGUCCCCUGCUAUCCCCCGCCUGCCCCAGGGGAGUUCCCUGAGGCCCACAGCCUCCACCUGUCUCUGCUGGGCGUCAACUACCCGCUCAGCCCCGGCCUCUUCUCCUACUUGGGGCCCUCACUGGCCGCUGCAGCCCAUGUGCCCUUCCUGGCCUCGGCCAGCCCCCUGCUGCCCCCGGCCACGGCCUUCCCAGCCGUGCAGCCCCCUCAGCGCCCCACCCCGGCCCCCCGCCUGUACUACCCGCUGCUUCUGGAGCACACUCUGGGGCUGCCAGCAGGCAAAGCUGCCCUUGCCAAGGCCCCUGUCUCCCCCAGGAGCCCCUCUGGGACUCCGGCUCCUGGCCUGCUGAAGGUGCCAGUUCCAGGGCUGGGGCCCUGGCCCCGAGUCACCCCCAGGGACCCAGGGCAGGAGGGGGAGCUGGAGCGGGCAGCCCAGAGUGACCCCAGGAGGAGGCUGUCCCUGGGAAGCAGGCUGGAGCUUCCGAAGGCAUCCCCCAGCCUGACAAGGUUCUGUUCCCGGAGCAGCCUGCCCACCGGCUCCUCUGUGAUGCUGUGGCCUGAGGACGGGGAUCCAGGCGGCCCUGAGACCCCCGGCCCUGAGGGCCCCCUCCCCCUGCAGCCACGGGGCCCAGUGCCAGGAAGCCCGGAGCAUGUGGGCGAGGACCUGACCCGAGCCCUCGGUGACUACGCCAGGGUGGAGCAGCGCCUGGGACAGUUGGGGCCCGCGGGGGGCCUGGCCCCGAGACCCCUGCGGGAGCAGCUGGGCAAGAUCCGCCUGGAGCUGCUCACCAUUCACCAGGCGCUGGAGCAGGCCGUGAGGCCGCCAGACGCACCCCUCGACCUCUCUGUGAAACGUGCGCCCGCCAAGGGGCCCCAGGCUCUUGGAGAGGCGUGGGGGCGGCCCGAGCUGGGUCCCGUGUUGACCGGGGGCACCCCCGAGCCACCCGGCAUGCUGGGCCCUGCAGCGCCCCAACCCUUCUCUGGCCACACCACCAAGUGUGAGGCCGACUCCAGCGUCCCACCCCCAGGGCUCCCCCUCGCAGCCCCAGAUGACCCUGUCAUUCCUGGCAGUGGCUGGGGCACCUGUGUUGCGACGAGGAGUUCCCAGACCCCUGAGGCUGUCUGUGGCCUGCAGAGCCCCCAGGGCGCCGAGGUCUGACCUGCAGCGCCUGAGGUCUGACUGUCUCUGCCUGCAGCAUGCCGGCCCCUCUCCUGCAGCCCCUGCCCCUCACCUGCCUGGGACCUGCCCCGCCUCCGCAUGCAUGUGGAUAGACCCCCACGGGCCGUGGCCAACGCUUGUCCCUGGGGCCACACAGGGACACUGGAGGUCACAGUUAUUUAUUGAUCACAAUUGUGGACAUUAAAACAGAAACUGUUCACA